AGUGGUCACGGAACUCGGCUGCGGCUCCAUGGUCUGAGUUGUCAGCCGUUGUUUUUUCGUGCUCGCUAGUCGCCGCCGCCGCUCCGCCAUGGGGAAGCGACAGCACCAAAAGGACAAAAUGUACAUUACCUGUGCUGAAUACACUCACUUUUAUGGUGGCAAGAAGCCAGAUCUCCCACAAACAAAUUUUCGUCGUUUACCUUUUGACCACUGCAGUCUCUCUCUGCAGCCCUUUGUCUACCCAGUCUGCACUCCCGAUGGCAUCGUCUUUGACUUACUGAACAUUGUUCCAUGGCUUAAGAAGUACGGGACCAACCCCAGCAAUGGAGAGAAGCUGGACGGGAGGUCCCUGAUCAAGCUGAACUUUUCCAAGAACAGUGAGGGGAAGUACCACUGCCCAGUGCUGUUUACCGUGUUCACCAACAACACCCACAUCGUGGCUGUGAGGACGACCGGCAACGUCUACGCCUAUGAGGCAGUGGAACAGCUAAAUAUCAAGGCCAAGAACUUCCGGGACCUGCUGACCGACGAGCCCUUCUCCCGGCAGGACAUCAUCACCCUCCAGGACCCCACCAAUUUGGACAAGUUCAAUGUCUCUAACUUCUAUCAUGUGAAGAAUAACAUGAAAAUAAUAGACCCAGAUGAAGAGAAGGCCAAACAGGACCCGUCUUAUUAUCUGAAAAAUACAAAUGCCGAGACCCGAGAGACCCUGCAGGAGCUCUACAAGGAGUUCAAAGGGGACGAGAUUCUGGCAGCCACCAUGAAGGCCCCGGAGAAGAAGAAAGUGGACAAGCUGAACGCUGCCCACUAUUCCACAGGGAAGGUCAGCGCUUCCUUCACCUCCACCGCGAUGGUCCCGGAGACCACACAUGAAGCAGCUGCCAUCGACGAGGAUGUGCUGCGCUACCAGUUUGUGAAGAAGAAGGGCUACGUGCGGCUGCACACCAACAAGGGCGACCUCAACCUGGAGCUGCACUGCGACCUGACACCAAAAACCUGCGAAAACUUCAUCAGGCUUUGCAAGAAGCAUUAUUACGAUGGCACCAUCUUCCACAGAUCCAUCCGGAACUUUGUGAUCCAAGGGGGCGACCCCACAGGCACAGGCACGGGUGGGGAGUCAUACUGGGGGAAGCCCUUCAAAGACGAGUUCCGGCCCAACCUCUCGCACACGGGCCGCGGCAUCCUCAGCAUGGCCAACUCCGGGCCCAACAGCAACAGGUCUCAAUUCUUCAUCACGUUUCGCUCCUGUGCCUACCUGGACAAGAAGCAUACCAUCUUUGGACGGGUUGUUGGGGGCUUUGACGUACUGACAGCCAUGGAGAAUGUGGAGAGUGACCCCAAAACUGACCGCCCUAAGGAGGAGAUCCGCAUUGAUGCCACUACAGUGUUCGUGGACCCCUAUGAGGAGGCCGAUGCCCAGAUUGCGCAGGAGCGGAAGACACAGCUCAAGGUAGCCCCGGAGACCAAAGUGAAGAGCAGCCAGCCCCAGGCAGGGAGCCAGGGCCCCCAGACCUUCCGCCAGGGCGUGGGCAAGUACAUCAACCCAGCAGCCACGAAGCGAGCAGCAGAGGAAGAGCCCUCAACCAGUGCCACUGUCCCCAUGUCCAAGAAGAAGCCCAGUCGGGGUUUUGGGGACUUCAGCUCCUGGUAGCAGCAGCAACUUGCAGGCUGUACCUCUGCCCUUCCUUUUCUCAUCAAUCACUGAUGCUGAAGCUGCAGGCCUGAGCCCUUUGUCUCCCUGGAUGCUGGGUGGCGCCUCAUCUGCAUCUCUGCCUCACCCCAUCCACUGCCACAGGCUGCCUGAUGACCACUAGAGGUAUGUCUGCCCCUCGUCACCCUGCUGCACACCAAUCUGUGGCCCUUCAUCAUGCUAAGAACAAGAACUGCGCCAUGGCUGGCUCCUUCUCUUCUCCAGCCCAUCCCUCUGCAGCCUGUCAUCCCUGUCUGUGACCAUUGGUCGGGCCCCUGGGCUCUAGAGUGACUUUUGACGCCCUCCAUCCCUCCCGCCAGGCACUGUCCUCCGCAAGGCCUGGUGCAGCCCUGGCAGUAACUGGCUUGUAAGAGGCUCAGACACCAAGCUGGGCCUGCAGAGGAGGGGCACAGUAGGACACAGUGACUGCCCAGGUGUCCACACACCUGUAGGCCUCUGAGCCAGCGUCCAGGGUACAGGUGCGGGUGGUGGGGAUGAAGGCCUGACCAGGGAGGGAGAAGCAGGUUUGGAGAGGACCCUGUGCCCACCCUGACAGACACCCUGGCUGGCCCUGACUGACUGUAUUCUCUGGCCACAUUCAAGUCCCCCAUUGGUGGGGGCAGAGAAGUAGGACCAGGCCAUCCUUGGCUCCAGAGCUCGAAGACCCCAAGACAGCCCUCUGCUCUCAGCGGCGCCACAGAGAGCCUGGGCUCAGCCUUCUGCAUCAGGACAUGGCCUCGUCCACUGAGGGCACGAUUUAAACAUUUGACAUCAGAAGCUUUAUUUGUAAACCUCACACAGAUAAGGACCAAGGGCUGGCGGUGUGGCCAGAGGACAGGGGAAGCUGAAGGCCCCGUGCUUGAGCUCGGCAGUCCUGCUCCUUGCAGUGAAGCCACCAUGGGUGACCGUCCAGCCUCACCCGGUGGCCUGCACAGUGAGGGAAGGGCUUCAGGGCCAUCUGCUCCCAGGGCAGGGGACAGGCCACCAAGGACCUUUGGCAAAUGAAGGUUUACAUUUCUGUAGUUUGUUUGUUUUAGAGCUUAAUUUGUAGUUUUUUAGCUAUUAAAACCAUUUGAAUUUUUAACGACCUGAUGAGGGCAUCAGGUAAAUUAAAGGAUUUUGGGAAGAUUCUUAUUUUCAAUUCUAAUAUCUGACAGAUGCCAUCAAGAAUAAGCAUUAAGGUAUAAAAAAUACUGUGUGUAUAAAACAAUGCCAAACCACAUUCCUACAGCAAAUGCACUGUGCCAUUUAUAACCCUGACAUCACCUCCCAAGGCUCUCAAGGAAGAUUUAUUUUAAAUAACUUAAAUAGAAGUCCUAGAUGAUAUUGUUUAGGAAUUUAAGAGGGUGGUGGAUAUGGUCCUGUGAAUAGCACUUCCCCUGAAGCCAGCUCAUGGUCUGUUCAUUUGGUUUAAAAAUGAGCUUGUAUUUUGCAGAAGCCCAACAAAAAAAAAGUGAUAAAAGUGUUGUUGGUAUAAAUUACAAAAAAAAAAAAAAAUACAAAAGUCAUAAGACUACUAGUAAAAAAUGUUCAAUCAAUGCCGUCACAAAAGACAGUACAAAAACCAAAGUGCCCAAAUAGAAGGAGCAGCGAACUUGCCCAAAACAGAAAAGCUCUAAAUAGAACUUUAGUAUAUACAAAAACCACUCGGUAGAGUUUUAGAAGUUUCUUCCAUGUAAGUGAAGCAUCUUGAGUCACUCAGGACUUGGCUGUCCUCGCACCCGUGGCAGGCUGGGGACGGCACGAACCUCCAACUGUUUCCCCUAGUCCCCGGGGCAUCGGAGGCUGGGUUCCCACAUGGGAGAGGAAUGAAGACUCACUCAAAGGGAAGGGUCAGUUUAAGAUAAGUUUUCAGUGAACUCCUUCUUCCACCCGGGAAGGUGUCUUUCAGCCUCUUCACAGUCUCAAGACAAUUGACUGAAGCCACAGGCAUUGCUAACUUCAUGGGCCAGCUUGUGGGCGGAGCCUCUUCAGGCUUGAGACCAUGGCAGCAAGAGCCCUGCAGCGUGCAGUGACCCCUGCGCUCUGGGUGGCUGCACGCGAGCUCAGGAGGACAGGAUGUGCUGGGCCAGCCUAAACCCUCGGGGGAGACUAGCGCAGGGAUAAAGCAGCUUGCAGGGCCAUAGCCGGAUGUGGAGGCUUCCAAGACAGUACAAAGAUUUCCUUCCUUUCCUAAGUGGAAGAUGUGCUUUAAAGGAACUUCUGCCUCUGUCACUCCUGCUGAGUGGAUGCAUCUCAGUGCCAUGCCCACCAGGGCAGCGGCAUUUCCCACCUGCCAAGGCUUCCAGGCUUGGGCAAAGAGAUGGCACCCAAAGGCAUGCUGUGUGUGGGCAGUGAGCUCGAGUGGGCACAGCCCAGUGCCUGCCUGGACCGCAGGUCUGGGUUUAGGAAGGGCUGAAGUCGGGGGAGGUGUGAAGCUGGGCAGGUGGCCACGUUCUUAUUGUCAGCCAGCUCGCACUCUUGCCCCUAGACUAGCCUUGUCUGAAGGCAGCUUCAGAGCCACUUGCCAGGCUGAGAACUAUCCGGGCUCAGUGCUCUCCUAUCUGCUGCCCCUCGGUCCCCCUGCCUGCCCUCUGCCCUGAGACAAGUUACUAAAUGUUGAAAACCAAACUUAUCUGGGAGUGGUUUUUGACCUCCAUCCUCUGCAAAGUGGCCUAAACCCUUAUGGGGUGCCCACUCCUGGUGGAGGGCAGGUGGAUGAGUGGAUUGUAAUUUAUAAUAAAAUAUAUGGCAGAAACACAGGCCUUAGGAGAUUGCACAGGCCCCUCUAUCAGUUCAAGUGACAUGGGACAGCACCACGCAGGGACGGGCAACGCGUCUAGCAGGCCAGGCGUCUUCAUGCACAAAGGCUAAACUUGUUGCUUUAACCUUUUCUGAACAAAUUUUAAACAUUCUGGCAAAUGUCAAGUUUUGAAGUUUUUCCUGUGGGUUCUGGCCUCUUUCAUAUGCAAAAAUAAUUCUUUUUCUUCAAGUACAUCCAGGGUAGAAAAUGAAAUCUGACUUUUCCUCGGUCCAGUGUGUUACUCUAUAGACAUGGACCAGCCACUCAGCAACUGCCUGACACCUAAGCUGCUGUCACUGCUGAGGGCACAACCCCUGGUACCAGACCCUGUGAGGCUGUCACCUCAGUAAGGGCACCUCUGCGGGCCCCGGGACAGCCUUCUCUAAGGGCUAGCUCACCUGCUUUCUAGAUAAGGAAUCUACUGGCUUAAAUAAACAUGUUCCACUAGACACCA